GCUUGGCCCCAUCUACUGAAUGUGCUAAAAGUGGGGUGAUGAGGGAUCCACCAAGAGGGUGGUGAGGAUUGAAGGGGGGUGCCAGUGUCUGGCAAGGGGCAAGUGCUCAUUGCGUGGGUGUAACAGUUAAGGCGAAGGACCCUUUUCACAGUGGACCCGGCGCGGGUCCCGGUCCACUUGGGAGGCUCUGAGCUGCAUGGAGGCUCUCCUGGUUUGUUCAAAUGGAGUGGCCACUUGUGAAUUCCAACUCCUUUUACUAUUUUUAUCUUUGAACCAAAACUUGUCUCCUGUAGGCACAUAUACUUGGAUCUUUUUUAAAAUGCAGUCUGGUAGUUUCUGCCUUUUGAUUGAAUUGUUUAGCCCAUGCACAUUUAAUAUUAUUGAUACACUGUAGUUAGGUUUACAUUUGCCAUUUUACUUUUUCUUUUCUUUAUACAAGUCUGUCUUUUUCUUCCCCUGUUCCUUCUUUAAGUGGAUUAAAGUGAAUAUUUCCUAAUGUAGCAUUUUAAUUUAAUGAUUUUUUUUCCACAACUUUUUUGGGUUUUUUCCAGUGCUUUAUGUUUUACCGUAUACAGCUUAAUCUUCAUAUUCUCCAUAUACAUCUUAAGCUUCAGAUUUGUACUAGGUUAAUUCCAAGUGAUACAGAAAUGUUACUCUUAUAUGGUUAUUUUUGUGGUAUUUUGUUAUAUGUAUUACAUCUGAUAAUGUUACAAACUCAACAGUACUGUGUUAUCAUUAUUACUUUCUGUCUGUGGUCAUUUCCUUAGCCAGCAGGGGUUUGCUUUCACCCACUUUGUUUUGUUAUUGGCAAAUAUAGUACAUGUCUGUAUAUAUUAUACACAUAUUACUGUAUACAAUUGCUUUUUAAAUUAAGAGAAGGAGGUAGAGGAAUAGGCAUUUAAACUAUAUAAGAACAUAAUUACCUUUACUGGUGCUGUUUUUGUGUGUGUGUGGUUUUGAAUUACUGUCUGGGGUCACUUGCUUUCAGCCUGAUGAACUUCUUUUAGUGUUUCUUGUAAAGUGAGUUUUGUUGUUGUUGUUGUUGUUGUUGUUGUUGUUGUUGUUUUUGCUUUGAGACCAGAGUCUCACUCUGUUGCCCAGGCUGGAGUGCAGAGGUGUGAUCUCGGCCCACUGCAACCUCUGCCUCCCGGGUUCAAGUGAUUCUCACCUCAGCCUCUGGAAUGGCUGGGAUUACAGGAGGCUGCCACUACGCCCGGCUAAUUUUUGUGUUUUUACUGGAGACAGGUUUUCACCAUGUUGGCGAGGCUGGUCUAAAACUCCUGACCUCAGGUGAUCACUGCCUCAGCCUCCCAAAGUGGUGGGAUUACAGGCAUGAGCCACCAUGCCCAGCCCAUUUUUGAAGUAUAGCUUUGCUGGAUAUAGGAUUCUUGGUUGACAAGUUUAUUUGAGCAUGUUGAAUAUGUUUGAAUAUUCUCCAUUGUUUCAGUCAGUUCAUUUAUUGAGGUUCCCUUCUAAGUGGCUUUCUUCUUGGGGCUUUCAAGGUUUUGUUCUCUUUCAAGAUUUUGCCUUUGAUCUUUGUAUUUUUACAGUGAUGUGUCUGUGGAUCUCUUUGCAUGUAUCCUAUUUGGAGUUCUGUUCAUUAAGAUUCCUGGAUAUGGGGCCAGGCACGGUGGCUCACGCCUGUAAUCCCAGCACUUUGGGAGGCUGAGGCAGGCGGAUCACAAGGUCAGGAGAUUGAUACCAUCCUGGCUAACACAGUGAAACCCUAUCUCUACUAAAAAUACAAAAAAUUAGCGGGGCGUGGUGGCGGGCGCCUGUAGUUCCAGCUACUUGGGAGGCUGAGGCGGGAGAAUGGCAUGAACCUGGGGGGCGGAGCUUGCAGUGAGCCAAGAUUAUGCCACUGUACUCCAGCCUGGGCGAUAGAGUGAGACUCCGUCUCAAAAAAAAAAGAUUCCUGGAUAUAUAGGUUAAUGUUUUUCUGUAAAUUUGAGAAGUUCUCAGCCAUUAUUUCUUCAAAUAUUUUUUCUGCUCCUUUCUCUCUGCAUUCCUGGUGGUUCUUAUUUUGUGUAUGUUAGUGCACUUAAUGAUGUCCAGCAUUUCUCUGCAGCUUGCUUUAUUUUUCUUCGUUCUUUUUUUCUCUGUGUUCUUCAGCAUGCAUAAUCUAUCGAUCUGUCUUCAAGUUUGCUUAUCCUGCCAGUUCAGUUCUACUAUUAAGCCCUUCUAGUGAAUUUUGUUAUUUCAGGUUUUGUACUUUUCUACUCCAGAAUUUCCAUUUGGUUUUUAAGUAAUUUAUCUUUAUUGAUAGUCUCUUUGAUGCAGCAUUAUCUUAUGUUUCUUCUUUAUUCAUGAUCUUGAUAUUGUUUAUCAUGGCUACCUUGGUCCUUUAUAUAUGUAUAAAUCCAACAUCUGGUCACUCUCACAGACAGCUUCUGUGGCCUGCUUUUAUUCCAGUGUAUGAGCCUACUUUUCUUUUUCUUUGAGUGCUUCAUAAUUUUUUGUUGGAAUUAUGCCUUCAUAAUUUUUUUGACAUUUUAGAUAAUACAUUUUAGCAAUUCUGGGUACUGUCCCCAACCCUGGGGCUUGUCAUUGUUAAUAUGCUUAUUUGUUUAGCAACUGGGUAGAUUGUUUUGAUAAAGUAUAUUUCCCCUGCCACAGUGUUCAGCCUGUGAUGUUGCUGGUGGGGGGUGGCACCCAGCCACUCUGGAUGACAGUGGUUUUAGUGAGGUCCUUUUCCUCUUUCCCUGACCACAUCCAGCUGUUGAACUUCGCUAAUGCCAGGUUAUUGUGCUGUUCUCAGCAACAGCCUGGGCAUAAGUUGCUCUACAAACUAAUCCAAUCAAAUUGUGGCUUCUUCGAAGGGAUACUUUCUAAGGUCAGUGUUUGGUUAGUUUGUUCUGUGUCCAAGAGGCCUCCUCCCAGCCGUGUUAGUCUCUGGUUCUCUUCUGCGAACUGGUUGGCCUACAAUUUGGCCUAUUGCUUGAUUCUCCACUGCCUCCACCCCCUUCGUCACAGCAUCCACGGUACUUGAACAGCUCCCUUAGGCCGGAACUUCUCCACAUUCCAUGGCAGGGAAUUUGGUGCCUUUGGGCAGGUGUAAGAGCUGUCUGUUUAGUUGCCUGCCUCUCAUCCCAGGCAGAGCCUCUGAGCCAGGGCCUGCAGCUGAGGACAGUAAUGGGCUCCUCUCUGAAUAGGGGCUGGGGGAGCUAGCAGCAGCCUGAGAUCCUCCAAAUGUGUCUUCCCCAGCCUGGAACCACCUCAUAUCUAGGACGGGGUUGAUGGGGCCCCAGUCUUCUCCGUUCACUGGGCGGAGCCUCUUGCAGAGGCUUAAACCGUACUGGUAGAAUGGAGCCAAGGUGAAGCCUUCAUUCUACAAAUAGGGUCUGAGCAGAAAGGAGGGCCCCUCUUCUCAAUCCUACUCACUCAGGACCUGGUCUCAGUCACAGGUGGGAUGAGAGCAGAAAGGGAAGCACUGCUAUCCUGCCUCUCCUGGGAAGACACCCCGCUGCCUGGGAGCUGGGGAGGUGGCCCUGUGUUCUUGGCUGCAGCAGGAUGGAGCUCAAGUGCCACAGACUCUCCGUGUCCUUACCAAAUGUAUGUAGGUGUUCUGGAGCAAGUGUUUCUUCAUUUGCUGGGUGCCCAUAGGACCAUUUCCAAAGGCUCUCUAAAUGGCUGUUUUGGGACUGCUCAUUACUCUCUGAGAAGGUCAGUGAAGCUCCUCGAGCCAUCAUGUUGAAGUCAGUCUCGGCCAGCCCUUUUGGAGAAACCAUGUUUGUGCUUCUGACAUACCAGUUAUUAAACAAUCUACUGGAAUGAGGAGAAUCUCAAUGAUGAGAAAGUCUUUCCUUUUUUGGACUGUGGGAGCAGUCCAAGCUGCCCAGCUGCAGAGCAGGAAUCUGCAAGUGAGACUGUGACCAAUUCUUGACAUUUUGGAGUUGACACCUUGGAGGUGGUUAAUCCAUGACGAAACUGAAGCUAAGCCGAUCUCAUGUUUUGACUCCUGUCAAUCCGGAGAGGACAGCAAAUGGCCUGCUCAGGUGUCUGUUAACAGCCAGCGCUUCCAGGCCCACCAGAUCCUCAGGUGUCUGUUAACAGCCAGCGCUUCCAGCCCAGCAGAUCAUCUGGCUUUUCUCUGCAGAAGGGGCCAAAAGGUCCACCUGAUGAACCUGUUGCACGCGAAAAGUUCAGAACCACUGCUGCCAAGAUGCUGACAGAAGCCUUGAGAAGCACCUGCUGCGGGAAAAGACGUGCAGGCGUAGAACACAGAGCGGGUGGCAGCUUCUUCAGUUCAAUCCCCACCUCAGGCAGUUGUUGGGGGUCAUAUCUAGGCUCACAGGUGCAGUGCGGUCUUCAGCGCGCUUGAAAGCACGAAGUUGUUCGGCAGCCAGGUUGGCCUCUGCCCAGGAAGUUGCUGGUUCCACGUCUGCCAAGACAGCAUGUCUGGUGAGCCCUGUUACCGUGGAGAACGCCAAGAUCCUGACUCGAGGGUCCAUUUUUAUACAAAAUUGCCACUCCAAGAUGUGUUGCUUUAGAAAAAUAUCGACUGUUACUUAUCUGCCAGAGGGGGACUAUUGCAGAUGAAAAGCGUGCUAUGGAGUCAUGCUGGCCCAUUGCCGUGCAGCCUCACCGCCAGAGGCUUGAAGAGAAAGGCAGAGUGGGUGGGGAAAGGAAUCUCAUGCCGUCUGCCGUUCACCCUAGCCCAGCCAUCGAUUCCGAGGAGCGAGUUCCUGAACUUACCGACUUCCUCAUCCCACAAAGCCACAGACACGCGAACGUCCAAGAAGUUCAAAUGUGACAAAGGACAUCUUGUGAAGUCAGAAUUACAGAAGCUUGUCCCUAAGAAUGACAGCGCUUCUUUGCCAAAAGUGACACCUGAGACCCCUUGUGAAAAUGAGUUUGCUGAAGGCAGUGCCUUGCUUCCAGGCAGCGAGGCUGGCGUUUCUGUGCAGCAGGGGGCUGCAAGUCUUCCUCUCGGUGGCUGCAGAGUUGUGAGUGACUCUCGCUUAGCAAAGACUAGAGAUGGCCUGUCCGUGCCAAAACACAGUGCCGGGUCCGGAGCAGAAGAAUCCAACAGCAGCUCCACUGUGCAGAAGCAGAAUGAGCCAGGGCUACAGACAGAGGAUGUGCAGAAGCCACCACUUCAGAUGGACAACAGCGUCUUUCUAGAUGACGACAGCAAUCAGCCAAUGCCCGUGAGCCGGUUCUUUGGAAACGUUGAGCUCAUGCAGGACCUCCCACCUGCGUCUUCAUCUUGUCCUUCAAUGAGCAGACGAGAGUUCAGAAAAAUGCAUUUCAGAGCCAAAGAUGAUGAUGAUGACGACGACGAUGAUGCAGAAAUGUAGGGGCCAUACAAAAUAAUGUCCUUGAGUAUUUAGUACCAUUAACAAUUUGACAAUUUAGCACAUUACAAGAUUUAUAUAAAAUGUAUCUCCAAGAGAAUGUCUUAAUCAAACUUCAGAACUGACCCAUCUAAGUCAAUAGUGCAAAGCACCCAAUACCUGUGGAGGAUGUACUCAUGGGAACUAAAACUCAAACCAUCUUUGAGGUUGCAAAGCUGCUGUACUGUGCCAAUGUCCUUUCUUUUUUUUUUUUUUUUUUUUUCCUUGGAGACAGAGUUUCUCUCUUGUCGCCCAGGCUGGAGUGCAAUGGCGCAAUCUCGGCUCACUGCAACCUCCACCUCCUGGGUUCAAGUGAUUCUCCUGCCUCAGCCUCCUGAGUAGCUGGGAUUACAGGCAUACACCACCACACCCAGCUAGUUUUUGUAUUAUUAGUAGACACGGGGGUUUCUCCACGUUGGCCAGGCUGGUCUCAAACUCCUGACCUCGUGAUACGCCCGCCUCAGCCUCCCAAAGUGCUGGGAUUACAGGCGCGAGCCACCAUGCCCGGCCAGUGUCCUUUCUUAUACACGUACAUACAUGAUGAUGGCUUGAGUCAGCUGCAGGGCAGUGGGCUUAAUGAGAGGGAUCUUUGUAAAGACAGCUCUUCACUUCAGCUCAGUAGCUUUGGUCAUAGGCAAGUUUGUUUUCCAUUAUCAUAAUUUGAUGAUUCUUGUGAUGAAUUCAAUGCUAGUUCUUAAAGAACUCUUUUAUUUCUGUAUGUGGAGCUAAUGUUUACCUUGGAAAUUUUGCAAAAUACAUGUAAGAAAGAAAUAAAAUAUAUUUUGAAAAUA